AGGCCUCACUAAGCUCCCACACAACCCAAAGGGCUGGUUUCACUCCCACUGUGGCCCACCCCCUACAACAGCACCAAGUCUGUUUUCAGGCAGUGGGCGAACAGGGCUGAGAACUUGCCCCAGGCUACCCACUUACCAGCUGCAAAACCAAGUAGGACGUUUGUUCUUCCCAGGCCUGUGGAGUCUGCACACUGAAUUCAUAUCUUUCUCCAAGUCCUGGCCAGGAGACUUCUCAAUCAGUUCAAACUGUUACAAAGUUCAGCUAGAGGUUUCCUGCUCCCUGUGGCCUUUUUCCAGUGCCUCUGACUGCCCCCCGCCCCAAGGACCCUGUGAGGCAGGGCAGAAAUGGCUUGCCAGGGGACCCAGUGAGUCCACAGGGCUUUUCCCGCUGCUUCCUCUACCCUGUAUUUUGUUUGGCUCUCUAAAUUGAUUCAACUCCAGUGCUUCCUCCAAAGGUUUAGAUAAUCCUUACCAGCAGAAGGGAAGACACCAACAUCCAAAUGACAUAGAACACUGGGCCUUUUCCUUCUACUCAAGACAGUGAGAUGGGAAAACUGAAUUCCAGACCUAACUGUCACCAACGGGACCAAUGACCGAGGGCAACAUUACAUGUAGUCACAUUUGCAAGAUGGGAGACCUGGAGUUCUGGAGUUCUGGACUAGAGCUGGCAACCUGGAUUCUGCAUACCUGAUUAGGUCUAUAAAAUGUCCUCAGGCAUAUAAAAUCCGUGCAUUAGAAGUCAAUUCUCGAAAGUCAAAACAUCAUAUAGGACUUUUGCUGACCAAAAACUAAAGGCUUCUGAGCAAGAUCACCAUUUGGAGACAGACUUAUCUAAAGAAAGAAAAGAGACUUCUUUUCUAGCCAAGAUGAAAGAUACACAAGACAUUCAGGAAGCUUCGAAGGCAAUGCAGAAUAAAGUCCAUGAGCAGGAAGAUAAGAAUGAGAAACAAAAACAAAGAGAAGACAAACUUGGAGUAUAUUCUUUAGUACAUUUUUCCCCAAAGAUGUUGGGUUCAGUUGCCACAACACUGCCAUUGUCAUCUUCAAAUUCCAGUGGAAUGCCUCUUGGUUACUAUCUGUCUAGUCCUCAGAUUAGUAGAGUAACUAUAUCAACAACUGGACAAUUGACUUCUAAAGCUACUGUAGGUAGCUGUUCCAGAGUGGAAAACAGCUUGGAUGCCAGCCCCUUCUCAGUUCCGAAGAAACAGGAUGAAUCACCCAUGAUUGGGGAUGGAGAAGAUUAUUUCCUUUCUUUGUUUGGUGAUUCAAAGAAACUUACAGCACACUCAAACUACACUCAGAAAACUUUAAAAUACUUUUCUAUGAUUCUUGAAGAAGUUGGCCAAUUUACCUCCAGUUCUCUUGGAGAUGUUGAAAUAGCUGAAGUGAAUGUCAAGGGUUUGUUCGUGAAGCUCAUUAACUCUUCCCUUGACAAAGAAAUGGCAAUUGGAGAUCAUAUUCUCCAGCAAAAUGUGAAUGGACAAACCAUUUCUUUGUACCGAUUCCUUCCAAACAUCGUAAUGCAGGCAAAUUCCACAGUAACAGUGUGGGCAGCAGCAUCUGAAGCAAAGCAUCAACCUCCAUCAGAUUUUCUUUGGAAGGAACAAGACAAGUUUAGAGCAAGUCCUGAUUGUAUAACAAUCCUGUGCAAACCGAACGGUCAAGCCAUUGCGUGGUACACCCCUAUCCACUGGAAGCAAGCGUGGGAAAAAUUAGAUGCUGACGUUGAAUUUAACAGAUGUUCAGUAGUAUCUCCAACAUUCCGAAAGCGUGUGUUUCAGUGGACAGCAUCUACAGCUACAAUAACUAAAGAAAAACAAGAUCAACCUAAGAAAGAUAUCUCAAAUUAUCAGGUGGAACAAGCUCAAGUUCUUCUUAAGAGAGAGAAGGAAAUCCCACCAACCGUUUUCCCUAAUCGCAGCCCUUGGUGCCAGAAUCCCUAUGUCUCUGCACAUCCUUACUGUCCUCUGAUUGAACCACACAAUACAUCCACCGCUGGAGGCAGAUUGGAUAGACAGCCCAGGACUCGGUCAACCAGACCUAAUCGAGCCUCAGGGUCUAAGAAAAAGAAGACAUCUGAGUCACAAAAGCAAUAAGCAGUCAACUCAACCUUUAAAGGACAAUAAUAUCCAAGUCUAGAGAAAAUGAAGAUGCCUAGCAUGUUGCAACCAACCUUCAUCACACAGGAGAGGAAGCCAGCAGCAAGCAAGCAAGAAAAUAGUUUCUUUUAGAUAAAAAAAAUAAUUCCUUAGGACUUUACUGUCACCAUUUCUGAAAGAAAAAGCUAGAGUUAGUGGACAAGUUAAAGUAUUUGUUUUCUAAGCAGUUGAGAAAAAAACAUUGGUCAAAAGCAAAACCAGCACAGUCUUUAUUUUGUUCACAUGAAGUGCCCUUGUGACUUCAGUCUUUUAUAUCCAACCCAACUAUCAAGUCUACAACUUCCACAGUUUCUACAGAUGCAUUUUCCAAAAGCAUAUGUGUCAGGAAUUAUGAAUCUUGGAGUCUGUCUGAUUCUCUACAGUUGGAAUCUGUCUCCUUGAAGUAUGGGGUUAAUUCAGCUUCCUAAUGAAAGAAUGAGUUAAAUUUCUACGGAGUAACCAGCUGGGAGUUUUUAAACCUGCCUACACUUAUCUAAAAUUUGCCAAAAAAGUCUCACCUUUCAGCUUGUGAUACUUACUAUGUGCAAAAUCCCAUGGACAGAACAGGAAAUGACAAAGGAACAAAAAUAUUUUAAUUAAAUAAUGUAAUGGAGCUACCUUUUAAAAAUGCCAUCCUCAGUCCUUAUUCUACAGCUAUCUUAUUCUAUACCUAUCAACAGUCUAAAAGUUUAAAAAAAUGAAAUAUGCCAAUUAUUAAUGUUGACCCUAUUUGUAGUGAGAAAGUAUGAUUGCUUCAGAUUCUGUGACAAUAUCCUGCCUAUUCCUUGUAGCUCUAUUUAAAUUGAUUCAUGUAUAUUUAUAUAGCAUAUACAGGAAGAUAUGGUGCAUACUUUCUUGGAGUUUGAGGGGAAGGAGAGAAGUGAGAAUUUUUCCCCAAUAUCUUCUUUUAAAAGAUUAAAAGUAAAAUAACCCAAAAAUUUUAUCAGUGGUGACCAUGAAGAGAAAUUCAUUGAGUUUUGUUGGUUUAUUACACCCAAGCACCAAGAGCUAAAAAUAUAUUUUUAAAAAUAUGCCAAGGGAUUCAAACAUAUGCAUUUUUUUUUUUUCAGAUGGAGUCUCACUCUGUUGCCCAGGCUGGAGUGCAGUGGUGUGAUCUCCACUAACUGCAGCCUCCGCCUCCCAGGUUCAAGUGAGUCUCCUGCGUCAGCCUCCCGAGUAGCUGGGAUUACAGGCAUCCGCCACCCUGCAUGGCUAAUUUUUGUAUUUUUAGUAGCAACGAGGUUUCACCAUGUUGGCCAGGCUGGUCUCGAAUUCCUGACCUCAGGUGAUCUGCCUGCCUUGGCCUCCCAAAGUGCUGGGAUUACACGCAUGAGCCACCAUGCCCGGCGCAAACAUAUGCUUUUGUUGCAGGACCUUUCCUUAGUUUAGCUAAAGACGGGGUUCUUGUCUGUUCCACAGCCAUGAAAAUUUAGGCUCGCAGAUGGUUAAAGGGUGAGUAAAGCAGGGUUUUAUUGGGUGAAAGGGGGGUUAAAUGGGAGAAACAGGGAUCCUCUGCAAGGCCAGUCCCCUGCUACAGUGCUUCCCGCCGGCCGUUGAAAUACCAGGUUCCACACAGGAAGAGGAGGGGCCGGUCUCAUCCUCGCUGCAAAGGGCAGGAACCCAAGGCUCCACCUCAGUUGCAGGCUGAUUGGAGUUUUUCCAGGGAACCCCUCCCACCUGGCUGACUCACUUUUGUACUAGUGUUCAUAGACUAUUAUUCACAAAAGCCCAAAAAUAGAAACAACACGUGUUCAUCGACAGAUGAAUGGGUUUUUUAAAAUCUGGUGUAUAAUACAAUGAAAUGUUAUUCAGUUAUUAAAAAAAUGAAGUUCUAAUACAUGCUACAACGUGGAUAAACUUUGAAACAUUAUGUUAAAUGAGAUAAGCCAUACACAAAAGGAUAAAUAUUAUGUAAUUUCACUUAUCUGAAUAAAAAAUGUAUAGAGAUGGAAAGUAUAACAGAGUUUACUAGGGGCUGUGCUGGAAAGGGGAGAAUGGAAAGCUAUUAUUUAAUGGGUAUAGAGUCUCUGUUGGGGAUGAUGAGAAAUAUUCAGGAAAUGGAUAGAGAUGAUGGUUGCACAACAUUGUGAAUGUACUUAAUGCCACUGAAUUGUACACUAAAAUGGUUAAAAUGGUUUACAAAGUACUUCUAAUAAAAUAUAGCUAGUAUUUCCAAGAUGGAAGAAAAUCAUAUUCUAGUCUCAAGCCUCUGAGAAGAUAUCCAUUGCUCAACAAAACAACUUUACGUAUACUUUCUGGUUAUACUGCAACAUAAAUAUUUUCUAGUUGCUGGGCCACACCGUUGACAUUAUUUCCUCAUUUUUGGACACUCCGGAGCAGACUUGUACAUUUUCAGAAAACUGUCAAUAACAUUUUUUGCCACUUUGCACCAUUAAGUGUUAUCUUUGAAUCAGGUGUUGGCCAAAUCGUGUAGACUGUUCCGUUUUGUUCAUGGUUACUAUGGAAACUGUGCAGUCAUAAUGUUUUGAGGAGACUAGCAGGAAAUUUAAGAGUGUACAAUAAAAGUUAACUUAUUUCAUGGUUUAAAA